GCAGAGUUCGAUGGAAAGCAAUGCAGAAGGAUGGGGGGUGGCGGGAGAGAGGUGAAGGGUAGGGUUUGCUCCAAUUUGCACUGAAUAUAAACCAGACUUUGGUAUCGGGGCAGGGAGUGAGCCAGAAGAAGGAAGGAAGGAGAAAGCAGGAGGAAUUAGCAAGCUGCAAAUUUAGCAAAUUAAGGAGAGUUCGGGGAGCCCAGGGUUAAACGGGAUGACUCCUCCUUCCCCCACCUCCGCCGAAGGGAAGGACCGGCGGGCGGCGGCGCGUGUGCCCGCGCCUGCGCCUGCGCCGGGGCCGGGAGUGCAUGGGGCGGUCGGGGCCGGAGCCGGCUGCACGGGAGCGCGCCCGGCCCGACCCGUGUGGACCCUGCGGGAAAGGAAGGCGGGCUGGGGACGUGUCUCCCGCCUGGCGGAAGGGGCGGGGGCGAAGCCGUGCGCGCUGCCGCCUCACCACCCUUGAUUUUACUUAUUCAAGUAAUAAGAAAGCAAAGAAGAGUUUGGCCAAAUCCUCUAGUCGCUCUCAUAGCUGAAGGCACCCACCGGGGCCACUUCUGUCCCCAGCGUCUUCUCGGGUCGUGCAGCCAUGGCCAUGCAGAAAAUCUUUGCCCGGGAAAUCUUGGACUCCAGGGGCAACCCCACGGUGGAGGUGGACCUGCACACGGCCAAGGGCCGAUUCCGAGCAGCUGUGCCCAGUGGGGCUUCCACGGGUAUCUAUGAGGCUCUGGAACUAAGAGACGGAGACAAAGGCCGCUACCUGGGGAAAGGAGUCCUGAAGGCUGUGGAGAACAUCAACAAUACUCUGGGCCCUGCUCUGCUGCAAAAGAAACUAAGCGUUGUGGAUCAAGAAAAAGUUGACAAAUUUAUGAUUGAGCUAGAUGGGACCGAGAAUAAGUCCAAGUUUGGGGCCAAUGCCAUCCUGGGCGUGUCCUUGGCCGUGUGUAAGGCGGGAGCAGCUGAGAAGGGGGUCCCCCUGUACCGCCACAUCGCAGAUCUCGCUGGGAACCCUGACCUCAUACUCCCAGUGCCAGCCUUCAAUGUGAUCAACGGGGGCUCCCAUGCUGGAAACAAGCUGGCCAUGCAGGAGUUCAUGAUUCUGCCUGUGGGAGCCAGCUCCUUCAAGGAAGCCAUGCGCAUUGGCGCCGAGGUCUACCACCACCUCAAGGGGGUCAUCAAGGCCAAGUAUGGGAAGGAUGCCACCAAUGUGGGUGAUGAAGGUGGCUUCGCACCCAACAUCCUGGAGAACAAUGAGGCCCUGGAGCUGCUGAAGACGGCCAUCCAGGCGGCUGGUUACCCAGACAAGGUGGUGAUCGGCAUGGAUGUGGCAGCAUCUGAGUUCUAUCGCAAUGGGAAGUACGAUCUUGACUUCAAGUCGCCUGAUGAUCCCGCACGGCACAUCACUGGGGAGAAGCUCGGAGAGCUGUAUAAGAGCUUUAUCAAGAACUAUCCUGUGGUCUCCAUCGAAGACCCCUUUGACCAGGAUGACUGGGCCACUUGGACCUCCUUCCUCUCGGGGGUGAACAUCCAGAUUGUGGGGGAUGACUUGACAGUCACCAACCCCAAGAGGAUUGCCCAGGCCGUUGAGAAGAAGGCCUGCAACUGUCUGCUGCUGAAGGUCAACCAGAUCGGCUCGGUGACCGAAUCGAUCCAGGCGUGCAAACUGGCUCAGUCUAAUGGCUGGGGGGUGAUGGUGAGCCACCGCUCUGGGGAGACUGAGGACACAUUCAUUGCUGACCUUGUGGUGGGGCUCUGCACAGGACAGAUCAAGACUGGCGCCCCCUGCCGCUCGGAGCGUCUGGCCAAAUACAACCAACUCAUGAGGAUCGAGGAGGCUCUUGGGGACAAGGCAAUCUUUGCUGGACGCAAGUUCCGUAACCCGAAGGCCAAGUGAGAAGCUGGAGGCUCCAGGACUCCACUGGACAGACCCAGGUCUUCCAGACCUGCUUCCUGAAAUAAACACUGGUGCCAACCAA